CUUUCUCCGCUGGCAACGGCGCCGCUCCCCGCUCCUCCUCCCCAGCCAUGGCGUUCACGUUCGCGGCCUUCUGCUACAUGCUGGCGCUGCUGCUCACUGCCGCGCUCAUCUUCUUCGCCAUUUGGCACAUUAUAGCAUUUGAUGAGCUGAAGACUGAUUACAAGAAUCCUAUAGACCAGUGUAAUACCCUGAAUCCCCUUGUACUCCCAGAGUACCUCAUCCACGCUUUCUUCUGUGUCAUGUUUCUUUGUGCAGCAGAGUGGCUUACACUGGGUCUCAAUAUGCCCCUCUUGGCAUAUCAUAUUUGGAGGUAUAUGAGUAGACCAGUGAUGAGUGGCCCAGGACUCUAUGACCCUACAACCAUCAUGAAUGCAGAUAUUCUAGCAUAUUGUCAGAAGGAAGGAUGGUGCAAAUUAGCUUUUUAUCUUCUAGCAUUUUUUUACUACCUAUAUGGCAUGAUCUAUGUUUUGGUGAGCUCUUAGAACAACACACAGAAGAAUUGGUCCAGUUAAGUGCAUGCAAAAAGCCACCAAAUGAAGGGAUUCUAUCCAGCAAGAUCCUGUCCAAGAGUAGCCUGUGGAAUCUGAUCAGUUACUUUAAAAAAUGACUCCUUAUUUUUUAAAUGUUUCCACAUUUUUGCUUGUGGAAAGACUGUUUUCAUAUGUUAUACUCAGAUAAAGAUUUUAAAUGGUAUUACGUAUAAAUUAAUAUAAAAUGAUUACCUCUGGUGUUGACAGGUUUGAACUUGCACUUCUUAAGGAACAGCCAUAAUCCUCUGAAUGAUGCAUUAAUUACUGACUGUCCUAGUACAUUGGAAGCUUUUGUUUAUAGGAACUUGUAGGGCUCAUUUUGGUUUCAUUGAAACAGUAUCUAAUUAUAAAUUAGCUGUAGAUAUCAGGUGCUUCUGAUGAAGUGAAAAUGUAUAUCUGACUAGUGGGAAACUUCAUGGGUUUCCUCAUCUGUCAUGUCGAUGAUUAUAUAUGGAUACAUUUACAAAAAUAAAAAGCGGGAAUUUUCCCUUCGCUUGAAUAUUAUCCCUGUAUAUUGCAUGAAUGAGAGAUUUCCCAUAUUUCCAUCAGAGUAAUAAAUAUACUUGCUUUAAUUCUUAAGCAUAAGUAAACAUGAUAUAAAAAUAUAUGCUGAAUUACUUGUGAAGAAUGCAUUUAAAGCUAUUUUAAAUGUGUUUUUAUUUGUAAGACAUUACUUAUUAAGAAAUUGGUUAUUAUGCUUACUGUUCUAAUCUGGUGGUAAAGGUAUUCUUAAGAAUUUGCAGGUACUACAGAUUUUCAAAACUGAAUGAGAGAAAAUUGUAUAACCAUCCUGCUGUUCCUUUAGUGCAAUACAAUAAAACUCUGAAAUUAAGACUCACUUUCAGUGCAUUGUUUGAGAUUAAAAAUAGUAUUUCUUAAACUUGCUUAAUCCAUGAUAAAGACAUGUUGCUGUCAUUUUUAAAAAGUGACGUACUACAUUAUGGGUUUUCUGAAAAAUACCAUGCCUAGAUCUAAAAAGGAAAAUUUUUAAAUGCCGAGCACAUUAACCUCUUUUGUCAUUUGACAAGAUUCAUAAACGUGGAUGGCAUAGCAUCAUCAUUUCUCUUACCAAUUAAGAAAAAUUAUGGUGGCACUUAAAAUAUUUUACUUUGAUUUUUCCUUUUUGGAACAGUCAGUUUUAAGGUAAAAUGGCUUGUAAAUUUGAGUUUUUGCUGCUGCUUGUAAGGCAGGUAAAUUAUGGCUUGCAUGUUUUCAUAAGCAUAAAUAAAUCUUGUGCUUUAUUUGGGAUGAGGAAGUUAAGGCAGUUGAAAAUAAAAUAAGUGGUUUGGAAGUUUCUUGAGAAGAGGAUCAAAAGAAAGAGAACCAAUAUAUAGAAAUUUCACAUGAUCAAGGAAGUUUAUGGAUGCGUUUGUGGAAAUCUUACUCUAUGAACUUGUUGGAUUAGAUGCUGUUUUAUUCUCUACUAAGUGAAAAGUGCUUUAUUUCAGUGCUUUCCCAUGGUUGGGAGAGAGUAGCUGUUAACUAUUCUGGGUAAUGGGGGUGAGUAUGUUGAGGAAGAGAUUUAGAACCAGAAGAGUGAAGAGACUCAAACUGUUCCAUAACAAGGAAAGCUUUAAAGACCUUGUAUUUCACAGUCUGGAGAACUAGAGGGAUCUGACUCUUGGUCAGUUCAUGUAACAAAUUAUUUAUUGAGUACUUGCUGGGCUCUCAAGAUUCAUGCUUUGAGCACAGGCAGUCAUUCAGUUUCCAGUCCACCUGAUUACAUCAGCAUGCACUUAGUUUUCUUUCUUGUUCACAAGGACUUUUGAUCAUGCAAGACCUGGCCAAGUCUUCUAUAAUCCAGAUGGGUUUCCUGGGGCUGUUACUUGAGUAUUCCUGUCAAAAUAUUUUCGUGAACCCUGCCUCUCUUAGCAAACACUACUUCAUAAGUGUUAACAAACAUCCUUUUAAUAAUCUAUUCCAGAAUAUUCUCCAGGAGUAAGUUUACUGGUUGGGAUUUGUGGAAGCCAUUUUCUCAUGUUUCCCAAAUAAGAUAUGUAGUCUUCAGCUGAUUCCUCAAAGAUGAUUGACAGGGAGUUUCACCCAUCUUUGUGGUAGUUUGUGAGUUCCUAGGCAUGUAAGUGAUUAAAAGAUUGAGUACCUGCUCUCCUAAUAUCUACCCACUUUUACCAUGUCAGUGUUUUAUGAAUUAGAUCACUUACCAAGAGAAAGCAGAAACGAAAUACUUGAAUCUGACAAUAUCCGACUGGCUCUUUUCAUUGCUCUGGAUUUAUUUUCCACAUCAAUCUCUUUGGGGUGGCCCUAGCCUAUUAUUCCUGUGGGUUCAGCUGAGGCAUGGUUAGCCUGGGUUUAUAAUUCAGUUUACGUUAAACAUUCCCUGUGCAGCAACAGCUGUUCAUUUAGGUACUCUUUUUUUUUUUCUCCUUAUUACAGUUACUUUUGGUAUUAUGUGCUUUAUCUUUAAAAGCUUUCUAGCUCUAGGAAAUUGUUUUCCCUGUUUGUGUCUAUUUUAUUGCAUCUUGUGUAACACUGUGGUUAUAUCUAUACCAACAACUUUUUGUUGCUAUGGAUACCACAGAUUGUCCUGAAUUAAAACCCUAACAUAAUAAAUGUCUGUUUAGCCGUUACUUUACUGAGUAAUAAUACUAUAUUGUGGCAGUAUGGCCCUUUAAUACUAAGGAGGUAUGGUGUAGAAAUUAUUUGAACACUCAUAUCCAAAUGUUAUUAAUGAUGUUUGACAGUUUUCUCAAUGCUUAAUGAUAUUCCUCACUCCUCAUUCCAGGGUAGAGGAGGGUUUGGUCCCAGGCUAUGGACAAACUGCUAAUUUGUUUGAAGUUUGAAUUAUUUUUCAUGGGAAAGGGAAGUGAUAGGAAAUGACCAAGACCAUCCACUUUUGACUUGAGUAUGGAUCGAGUAUAAGUAAUAGUUUCCUAGCCUCACUGAUUGUACCAUGAACUGACAGACCUACCAGUCAAAUUCAUGUACCCAGAUAAUGGUCUCUCACAUGGCAACAAAGUACACAGCAGUUUGCAGUAUGUGUCUCUUUUAAAGCCAGUUCAGUGUUUUCACCUUGACGACCACUCCUGCAAACAGUUCUCAUAGAGCUCUUCUCUGCUCCCCAAAUCAAUAUAUUUUGAAGCUAUGUCAAAUAUUUACAUAGAAAGGAAAUAAAGUUGUAUGUGCUUUGAAACCAGCAAAAUCCUUUGUACAACACCUCUCUUCUCCUUCUAUGUUUAUGAAUAGAGUUCGUGGAAUAUUGCCAUAGUGCAAAUAAUGACUUCCGUGUAUCACUUAUACCCUGUAGGGGUGAGCUUUCACCUUAGGUGUGGUUAUAUCCUAGCAGUGUAUCAAGCCCACUCAAAUAAUGGUCUAUAUUUAAAAGUAUGUGUCUAGUUUACUUAUUUAUGUCAUUUAACAUCCAUAAAUGUACAUCUCUCAGUUGUAUAUCAUGAUUGUAAAUCAGAAAUUUUGAUGGCAAAAAUAUUCUAAAACAACAUUCUUCAGGGGAAAGAAAAACAUGGAUACCUUAUCUAGCAUUGCUCAUAAAAGUACUCAUGUUCAUCCUUUUUGGAAACUAUUAAUCAUGCUAGCCUUAGAUCAUUUUAAGCUCCUUUGCUCAAACCAAUCAUUGAUGUGCAGUAUGACCAGCAGCUAGUAAGUCUGUGGUGCUACCAGUAUAGCUUGGAAGAUGGUUCUGAAUUAAUACCUCAGAAUGAUAUCAAAAGUAAAAGAGUGGUUCUAUUGCUAAAUAUAUUGACUAGCUUUCUUAUAACAAUUUUACUUUGAAAUUCAAAGUUCCAAAGCUAAAUGUCUAAAAGAAGUAACUGCAGCUUGUUCUGCUGAUUUUGGAAAAUAGUAUUAACCAUGUAAGAUCUUUGGGGUUGGAGUGAAGGUCUUAUCUGCAUUAAUUUUGUUAAUGCACAUUGUAGAUGUGGAGAACAUCUUGACCUGCAUAAGGAUUGCGUCUCAUUUUAUUGUGUAGUGCUUUUUCGAAAUAUUUACAUUUCUUUGGUUCCCAUGUUCAUGUAUUCUGGAGAAGUAAAAUUUCUUGAUUACUGGGCAGACCCUAAAACUACUAAGAGAAACAUAACAUGUAGUUAGCUGUCUGCUCAUGGUUUGUUCAAAUCUAAGCUAACCUUAAUGGUGCUGUGUCCGCUGUCCACAGAAAACGCCCUUAAGUAGCCCUACCUUACUCCUUAGAGCUUAUUUUGCUUUUGUAUUUAAUAAAAGCUGUCUUAAAUGUU